GGUUUCCAAACGUCGGCAGAGGCUGGAGACGGCUCUCUAGUGCUGGGUGUGGAGUGAGGCACCACCCUUGCCCUGAAGCCUGGGGCACUCAGUCACCAUGGCUCAUGCCCCAGAACCGGACCCGGCCGCCUGCGACCUCGGGGAUGAGAGGCCCAAGUGGGACAACAAGGCCCAGUACCUCCUGAGCUGCACUGGGUUUGCCGUGGGACUGGGGAACAUUUGGCGGUUCCCAUACCUGUGCCAGACCUAUGGAGGAGGGGCCUUCCUCAUCCCCUACGUCAUCGCGCUGGUCUUCGAGGGGAUCCCCAUUUUCCACGUCGAGCUCGCCAUCGGCCAGCGGCUGCGGAAGGGCAGCGUCGGCGUGUGGACGGCCAUCUCCCCGUACCUCAGUGGAGUAGGGCUGGGCUGUGUCACGCUGUCCUUCCUGAUCAGCCUGUACUACAACACCAUCGUGGCGUGGGUGCUGUGGUACCUCCUCAACUCCUUCCAGCACCCGCUGCCCUGGAGCUCCUGCCCACCGGACCUCAACAGAACAGGGUUUGUGGAGGAGUGCCAGGGCAGCAGCGCCGUGAGCUACUUCUGGUACCGGCAGACACUGAACAUCACAGCCGACAUCAAUGACAGUGGCUCCAUCCAGUGGUGGCUGCUCAUCUGCUUGGCAGCCUCCUGGGCAGUCGUGUACAUGUGUGUCAUCAGGGGCAUUGAGACUACAGGGAAGGUGAUUUACUUCACAGCUUUGUUCCCUUACCUGGUCCUGACCAUCUUUCUCAUCAGAGGGCUGACCCUGCCAGGGGCAACAAAAGGACUCAUCUACUUGUUCACUCCCAACAUGCACAUUCUCCAGAACCCCCGGGUGUGGCUGGACGCAGCCACCCAGAUAUUCUUCUCUCUGUCCCUGGCCUUCGGAGGACACAUCGCUUUUGCAAGUUACAACUCGCCCAGGAAUGACUGCCAGAAGGAUGCGGUGGUCAUCGCCCUGGUCAACAGGAUGACCUCCCUGUACGCGUCCAUCGCUGUCUUCUCUGUCCUGGGGUUCAAAGCAACUAAUGACUACGAGCACUGCCUGGACAGAAACAUCCUCAGCCUCAUCAACGACUUUGACUUCCCAGAGCAGAGCAUCUCCAGGGACGACUACCCAGCCGUCCUCAUGCACCUGAACGCCACCUGGCCCAAGAGGGUGGCCCAGCUCCCCCUGAAGGCCUGCCUCCUGGAAGACUUUCUGGAUAAGAGUGCCUCGGGCCCGGGCCUGGCCUUCGUCGUCUUCACGGAGACCGACCUCCACAUGCCGGGGGCUCCUGUGUGGGCCAUGCUCUUCUUCGGGAUGCUGUUCACCUUGGGGCUAUCGACCAUGUUCGGGACCGUGGAGGCGGUCAUCACACCCCUGCUGGACGUGGGGGUCCUGCCUAGAUGGGUCCCCAAGGAGGCCCUGACUGGGCUGGUCUGCCUGGUCUGCUUCCUCUCCGCCACCUGCUUCACGCUGCAGUCUGGGAACUACUGGCUGGAGAUUUUCGACAAUUUUGCCGCUUCCCCGAACCUGCUCAUGUUGGCCUUUCUCGAGGUUGUGGGUGUCGUUUAUGUUUAUGGAAUGAAACGGUUCUGCGAUGACAUUGCGUGGAUGACCGGGAGGCGGCCCAGCCCCUACUGGCGGCUGACCUGGAGGGUGGUCAGUCCCCUGCUGCUGACCAUCUUUGUGGCUUACAUCAUCCUCCUGUUCUGGAAGCCACUGAGAUACAAGGCCUGGAACCCCAAAUACGAGCUGUUCCCCUCGCGUCAGGAGAAGCUCUACCCGGGCUGGGCGCGCGCCGCCUGUGUGCUGCUGUCCUUGCUGCCCGUGCUGUGGGUCCCGGUGGCCGCGCUUGCUCAGCUGCUCACCCGGCGGAGGCGGACGUGGAGGGACAGGGACGCGCGCCCAGACACGGACAUGCGCCCGGACACGGACACGCGCCCAGACACGGACAUGCGCCCGGACACGGACAUGCGCUGAAGCCGGCCGGAGCGGGGCCUGCAUGGGCGGGUCUGUGGGGGGGCUUGGCCUGAUGGUGGGCGGGGCCCCGCCCACAGGGCCGACCCCAAUACACCAGCGACUCAACCUUGA